GCCCCAGUCACUGAGCCGCCGCCGAGGAUUCAGCAGCCUCCCCCUUGAGCCCCCUCGCUUCCCGACGUUCCGUUCCCCCCUGCCCGCCUUCUCCCGCCACCGCCGCCGCCGCCUUCCGCAGGCCGUUUCCACCGAGGAAAAGGAAUCGUAUCGUAUGUCCGCUAUCCAGAACCUCCACUCUUUCGACCCCUUUGCUGAUGCAAGUAAGGGUGAUGACCUGCUUCCUGCUGGCACUGAGGAUUAUAUCCAUAUAAGAAUUCAACAGAGAAACGGCAGGAAGACCCUUACUACUGUCCAAGGGAUCGCUGAUGAUUACGAUAAAAAGAAACUAGUGAAGGCGUUUAAGAAAAAGUUUGCCUGCAAUGGUACUGUAAUUGAGCAUCCGGAAUAUGGAGAAGUAAUUCAGCUACAGGGUGACCAACGCAAGAACAUAUGCCAGUUCCUCGUAGAGAUUGGACUGGCUAAGGACGAUCAGCUGAAGGUUCAUGGGUUUUAAGUGCUUGUGGCUCACUGAAGCUUAAGUGAGGAUUUCCUUGCAAUGAGUAGAAUUUCCCUUCUCUCCCUUGUCACAGGUUUAAAAACCUCACAGCUUGUAUAAUGUAACCAUUUGGGGUCCGCUUUUAACUUGGACUAGUGUAACUCCUUCAUGCAAUAAACUGAAAAGAGCCAUGCUGUCUAGUCUUGAAGUCCCUCAUUUAAACAGAGGUCAAGCAAUAGGCGCCUGGCAGUGUCAAGCCUGAAACCAAGCAAUACCGUCAUGUUUCAGCCAAGCCCAGAGCCCUAAGAUUACAAACAACUAUGGCCGGAACCUCCUCAGCUCUCCCUCUGCAGAGUUCCCUACCCUAAGAGAAUGUUACCACCUGAACAGUCCUCGGUGAAUCUGAGAGGAGAGGAUGGGGUAAGGCAGAAGCACCAGCUGUACUACUAGAAGGGAGCUUUUGGUGGUAGAUCCCCUGGUGUCUCCAACCUGACUAGGUGGACAGAGCUCAAAGAGGCCCUCUUACCGCUAGCGAGGUGAUAGGACAUCUGGCUUGCCACAAAGGUCUGUUCGACCAGACAUAUCCUAGCUAAGGGAUGUCCAAACAUCAGAAUGUGAGGCCAACCUUCUAUCAGAGUUAAACUUUUGACAAGGGAACAAAUCUCAAACUGAUCCAUCAGUCAUGUAGCUAGCUGUAGAGCUUGCAACUUAAUAGCAGCAGCUGCCCAAUGCCAUGUGAAGUAACAAACUGGUUUUUGGUUUUUUUUUCCCCUUCAGUUUUAAUGUUAUGUGUAAUGUAUUUAAACCCUUAUUUAAAUAAAACUUGUUUUCAGAAAUACCUGACUUGCAGAUUAUUUAUAUAUAGUCGAUCUUGUGCAUAUAAAGGAACCAUAGAAAUGGGCAGUGGAGGAUUCGUCCACACCCACAGCUUCUCAACGGGCCUGAAUUUGGCCAAGAAAAACCUUUAUGAGCUUGUCCCUCUCUGGUCAACUGGUUUUUUGUUCGUUUGUUUUUUGAGACAGGUUUGCCCUUGUUGCCCAGGCUGGAGUGCAGUGGCACAAUCUCGGCUCACUGCAACCUCCACCUCAGGUUCAAGCAAUUGUCGUGCCUCAGCCUCCCUAGUAGCUGGGAUUACAGGCACCAUGCCCAGCUAACUUUUGUAUUUUUAGUAGAGACAGGGUUUCUCCAUGUUGGCCAGGCUGGUCUUGAACACCUGGCCUCAAGUGAUCUGCCUGUCUUGGCCUCCCAAAGUGCUGGGAUUACAGGCAUGAGCCACCAUGCCCAGCAGGUCAACUGUUUUUGCAAGCAUUUAGCCAGAGUCAUGCUGUGCUGUUAAUCAGUGUCCUGGAGAAUGGGUUGCUUGGAAAUCUUGGCGCCCCCUCAGUAGUAACAGCCUUGGUUUAAGGGCGCAGAGUGGAGAGUAAAUGCAAGGGCUAUAACAAGGGCAUUCAUGCUGUGGGUUAAGAUCCACAAAUCGCUAGGAAUGUGUAUACUCUGGGUAGUAAGUUUGUAGUAUUAGAAGGUUUAAUGACAAGUAUUUGAAGAGCUGAAGUUAAGUGUUGGGAGGCCAUCCCUUAUGAAGGACAAUGAAUGGCAAGUAAAAGACCAAGUUCUGUUCCUGGGUCCAUUAAUUUAGUUAAAAAGGCAAAGUUCUUUCAGCACACAUAUCUGCAUGCAGUCACGUGCUGCCUAAGGAUGCUUCAUUCAACAAUGAGCCUCACAGCCGUGCUACACAAUAAGAUUAUAAUACUGUAUUUUUACUGUACCUUUUAACAUUGUGUUACAAUGGCCUACAAGAAGCUUGUGUGGAUGGCUUUGAAUGUGGCCCAACACGAACUAAUAAAUUUUGCUAAAACAUGA